AGGCAGCCGCCGCGGUCCCGGACCUCUAGUCCCGCACUCCCAGCUGGCGAGCCGGCUCCGGGUGCGGCGAGGCCCAGCCCUCUCGGAUUGCGCGCCGGACCCCGGGACGCGCUCCAUGCGGCCGCUCAGCAUGUCCGGGCACUUUCUGCUCGCACCCAUCCCCGAGUCCUCCUCGGACUACCUACUGCCCAAGGACAUCAAACUGGCGGUGCUGGGCGCCGGCCGCGUGGGCAAGAGCGCAAUGAUCGUGCGCUUCCUGACCAAGAGAUUCAUUGGAGACUAUGAACCGAAUACAGGCAAGCUGUAUUCACGGCUGGUCUAUGUCGAGGGGGACCAGCUCUCCCUGCAGAUCCAGGAUACUCCCGGGGGCGUCCAGAUCCAAGACAGCCUCCCCCAGGUCGUCGAUUCCCUGUCCAAAUGCGUGCAGUGGGCCGAGGGUUUUCUGCUGGUCUAUUCCAUCACAGACUAUGACAGCUACUUGUCCAUCCGACCCCUUUAUCAGCACAUCCGGAAGGUCCACCCUGACUCUAAAGCCCCUGUCAUCAUCGUGGGCAACAAGGGGGACCUUUUGCAUGCCCGGCAGGUGCAGACACAGGACGGUAUUCAGCUAGCCAAUGAGCUGGGCAGCCUGUUCCUUGAAAUUUCCACUAGCGAAAACUACGAAGAUGUCUGUGAUGUGUUUCAGCAUCUCUGCAAAGAAGUGAGCAAGAUGCACGGCCUCAGUGGGGAAAGAAGAAGAGCCUCCAUCAUCCCUCGGCCCCGCUCUCCCAACAUGCAGGACCUGAAGAGACGCUUCAAGCAGGCUCUGUCUCCCAAAGUCAAAGCCCCCUCUGCACUGGGGUGAACUAUCUCAGACAGAUGCCUCUCCUUUUUAAUACGCAUUUGUGCAGCUAAAAGACUGGGCUUCUCGCUUUUUAAUCACACAUUCAGAGUUUAUUUUUAUAAAAAAAUUGAUUUUCAAGUACAUGUGUAUUUCUGAAAAUUCAAACAGUGAUUGCCUAGAAGCUGGAUAAAAUUUUGUUUUGUUUUAUUAAAAGAACUUUUUUUUUUUUUUUUUUUUUUUUUUUUUUACUGUAACUGCUGGCCACUUUUCCAUUAAAGGCAAAAUGGCAACAUUGCUCAUUGUUUUCUCAAUGUCUUUUUAUAGAAAUUGUACUUGCACCAGCGCCCAGUGCUGCUCCAUGCUUGCCCUCAGUCUGAACUCUGAUUGGUGUCUCGCAGUGGGGAGGAGUUCAUGUAGAGGGAGUCUGUUGUGGGAGAAAGGAAAGUAUGUGGAGGAGGAGAGGGAUUUUAAUAACGGCAGGAGGUCUUUAAAUGGGACACUGCCACCAGUCAUGAAAUUGACACUGUGUGAUUUUCAAGGGAAGGGGUACAAUGCUAAAACGUUACAAGCCAUGAGUAACAUUUAUUGGUGCAAAUGCAAGUUUAUACUCUACCCAUAUUAAAAAACAACCCCUUUUCUAGUAUUCCUUAUGUCAGUAAGUGGACCCUACCACCCAAAAGUUGCCUCAAAAUUCUCCUUCCCUUCCAAUAGGGCACCAGAUAUGUCCAUCCUCACUCCUGUUUUUCUCUAAAGCCUCACUGUCCCUUAAUCUAGACCUCCCUUUGACUGGCAGGCAAGAAUCUAGGCAAGACUCAUGUUUCUUGCCUUCUAGAAUGACAUCUCCUAAUUGUCUCUUCACAUCAGAACAAUGCUACUAAAACUAACCCUAAUCAUUUUAUUUCUAUAAAAAACCCAGCUGGUUUCCCCUUAGCUACUGGUUAAGAUAGACAUGAGACAUGGCAUCAAGAUUCUUUACCACCUCUCCAGGCUUAUCAACCCCUCCUUCCAAAACACACACCAGCAGUCAGUCCAUUCCAACAGAUUGUCUUUCUCAGCUGCUCCAGGCUCUUUCAUGUCUUCCUGCCUUGGCACAAACUAUCCCUUUGCCUCAAAUAUUUUUUCUGAUUCUACACAUAAUGGCUUGCUAACUCAUCUUUAAAAACCCAAGUCACAUGCUAUAUUCAGCUCUGAAAUGCCUUCUCUGGUCUUCCUCUAUUCCUGGAGCAUUUGUGUUAUAACCCAACCCUGUCAGGUAGCUAUUUGUUACUCCAUUAGAAGGAGUCCCCCUCGAGGGCAGUAGCUGCAUUUUAUGAUCCUGUCUUCCAAUCUUCUAGUUCAGUGCUUCCCCAUAGAGUGGUAAGUUUUAAGUAAACAUAUAAUGAAUAAAUGAAUGAAUGCACCACUUAUGGUGCCAAGGGUCAAUGAUGGGAGAUUACCAUGAAACAAAUUGUUACUUCUGCAGGGCAAGGACAGGUGUUCUGAGUAAUUAAAGAUAGCUGUGGUGGAAAGGGACUGACAUAUGCAGCUUCUGGCAAUCACAGACCAUUACCCUUCCAAAAGGACAGCUCUGUCCAGACCUGUGAUGUCAGCACCACUUUUCCCUGUAGUUGAAGGGAGUCUACCUAUACAAAAUGGCAUGAAGGGUUAAGAAAAUUAGAUGAUGCAUGUCUAAAAGAGUGUCCAAAUAAAAUAUUAAUUUGGAUUCCAUCUUUUAAAAAA